GGCGGGGCUGCGGGACCGCGAGUGAGUGUGGUCGCUCCUGGUUCUGCCAGCUCCCCUGAGAGCCUGAACCCGGGCUUGAGAGCCUCGCCACCCCGGGUGACAUCCCUGCCGUGGGCUUGGGGGCUCUGGGUGUGAUUCCGCCGGUCCGGGUCCCGCAGCGACCACCUACCCAGCGCAGUCAGGGGCGGGGCUGGGACCCAGAGCGGGACCCCGGCUGCCGAGUCCAGGUGUCCCGCGGGCCUCGAUUUGGGGAGCAGAAAACGCCAGGUCUUCAAGGGUGUCUGCCACCACCAUGCCUGACCCAUUUGGCAGCAGCCUCGUGUGUGGUGGUCUGGUGUGGACGGUGGAAGCGUGAUUCUGCUGAGUGUCAGUGUGACCACUCGUGCUCAGCCGUAUCUCAGCAGGAGGACAGGUGCCGGAGCAGCUCGUGCAGCUAAGCAGCCAACUGCAGAAACGUCAGGUGUCCCAUUGCUGGCUCUGCCACGGAAACUCUCCAAAGGGCUCUCUCUACCCACUCCUGUGAGCUUUUUCUCCACCGGAAACUGUGUUAAGGUCACCUUUGACUUCAUCAUUGUUCUGCAGGUUACCACUCCCCCUUUUAAAAAGAUUGUGGUGAAAUAAUACAUGACCUAAAAUGCGCCAUUUGAACCACUGUUCGGCGUGCAGUGCCGUGGCAUGAAGUAUGUUCACAGUGCUGUGCGGCCAUCGCCACCUUCCGUCUCCAGAACUGAGCCCCGCUCUUCCCUCCCAGUCCCCGGCAGCUGCCAUUCUGCUCUCUGUCUCUAUGGCUUUGAGGACUCUAGGUACCUCCUAUUUAAGUGGAAUCCUACAGUGUUUAUCCGUUUGUGACCAGUGUAGAUCAUUUCGUGUAAUGUCCUUCAGUUUCAGCCGUGCCGUAGCUUGUGGCAGGGUUUCCUUCCUUUUUAAGGCCAUGUGACAUUCCAGUCCCACCUUGCUAAAGCAGUUUACCUGGUCACUGGGGUGACUCUGGAGCUCCCCUCUGGCCUCACUGCCUGUGCUUGGUCAUGUUGGCUAGCUGUCCUCCCUUCUCCACCUCUGAGUCUACAAGGGCUGCACUCCACGGAGGUCCCAUGCGUCAGCCCCGACCGCAGCGCUUGGCUCUGCUGCUGUGUCCCGUCCCCGUGAAGGCUCAGCAGGCACUCACUGGGCCUUCUCCCCUGCUCACUGCUCCGCACUCUGCACCCCACCCGCACUGUGCGUCUUCACCCUGCCUGGCCUGGGCCACUGUCCCUUCCUGCUCAGAUCAGUCAGCAGGGUGCCUCAGCUUGUUCCCCACCUCCACCCUGGCCCCCUGCCAUCUUUUCUGCACAUGGGCAUGAGUGAACCUAUUCAAGUGAAAUUCACAUUUUCUCAUGUCUCAUCAGAACCCCCAAAGCCUCCCCAGUCUCUGAUAACACAUCCAGGGUCUUUCGGUGGCCUGGAGGAGCUAUAAGAUCUGCUUCCUACAGCCUCCACCCUGUCUGCUGCUGCUCUUUGGACACCGGACCUUACACACCCCUCAGACAGUACAGCACCCACCCUGCCCUUCAACUCUUGCUUGGCCCCGUAAGCCAGUCCUUCCAGGCUCCUGCCUCCUCUGGUCAUUCCCUGCGUGGGCCUCUCGCAGGAAGCAGUUUUCCUGUGUCCCCCGCCGACCCCCUGCAGGAGGUAAGCUGCAUGAGGGCAGUAUCAUGUUGCCUAGCACCUUGGCCCACAUGGAGCAGGUGCCAAGCAGAUAUGUAUUGGGUGGAGGACCCUCUCCCUGUGGCCUUUUAUCUAUUUGUUCUCACAGGGUUUGCCAGGUUUGGCUGCAGUUCAUGUCACUUGAGGACAUUCCUUUCCAGCGCCGUUGGCUUUGUGGCUGUGGCUCUGUCACAGCUCCAGCUGUGCUAUCAUUGGUCCACAUUGUCCCCUCCCCUAUUUGCUGUGACUCCCAUGGGAAGAUCCUAUCUCUGUUCCUCUCGCACUGGGGCAAAGCAGUGCUGGCAGGGGGCUGGGGAACUGGCGGGUGGCCUCUCCUGGGCAGGAAGUCCAUGGCACCCAGGUGCUCCCUGUGCUCCAGAGGGGCUGGGGAGGUUUCAUGGAGUCAAUAGGCAUUGGCAAGCUGACAUGUCCCCUGUCCCACGCAGGCCUGUUGCAGUCUCCAAGGCACCAUGAAUGCCAUCGUGGCUCUCUGCCACUUCUGCGAGCUCCACGGCCCCCGCACUCUCUUCUGCACGGAGGUGCUGCACGCCCCACUUCCUCAAGGGGAUGGGAAUGAGGACAGUCCUGGCCAGGGUGAGCAGGCGGAAGAAGAGGAAGGUGGCAUUCAGAUGAACAGUCGGAUGCGUGCGCACAGCCCCGCAGAGGGGGCCAGCGUCGAGUCCAGCAGCCCGGGGCCCAAAAAGUCGGACAUGUGCGAGGGCUGCCGGUCACUUGCUGCAGGGCACCCGGGAUAUAUCAGCCAUGAUAAAGAGACCUCCAUUAAAUACGUCAGCCACCAGCACCCCAGCCACCCCCAGCUCUUCAGCAUUGUCCGCCAGGCCUGUGUCCGGAGCCUGAGCUGUGAGUGCAGGGAGAGUGCAGUGGCUGCUCUGACCUGCUGGUUCUUCUGCAUGCUCCAGGUCUGCCCUGGCCGUGAAGGCCCCAUCUUCUUCGGAGAUGAGCAGCACGGCUUUGUGUUCAGCCACACCUUCUUCAUCAAGGACAGCCUGGCCAGGGGCUUCCAGCGCUGGUACAGCAUCAUCACCAUCAUGAUGGACCGGAUCUACCUCAUCAACUCCUGGCCCUUCCUGCUGGGGAAGGUCCGGGGAAUCAUCGAUGAGCUCCAGGGCAAGGCGCUCAAGGUGUUUGAGGCAGAGCAGUUUGGAUGCCCACAGCGUGCUCAGAGGAUGAACACAGCCUUCACGCCAUUCCUACACCAGAGGAACGGCAACGCCGCCCGCUCGCUGACAUCGCUGACAAGUGAUGACAACCUGUGGGCGUGCCUGCACACCUCCUUUGCCUGGCUCCUGAAGGCGUGUGGCAGCCGGCUGACCGAGAAGCUCCUGGAAGGUGCUCCGACCGAGGAUACCUUGGUCCAGAUGGAGAAGCUCGCUGAUUUAGAAGAGGAAUCAGAAAGCUGGGACAACUCUGAGGCUGAAGAGGAGGAGAAAGCCCCUGUGUUGCCAGAGAGUACAGAAGGGCGGGAGCUGACCCAGGGCCCGGCAGAGUCCUCCUCUCUCUCAGGCUGUGGGAGCUGGCAGCCCCGGAAGCUGCCAGUCUUCAAGUCCCUCCGGCACAUGAGGCAGGUCCUGGGUGCCCCUUCUUUCCGCAUGCUGGCCUGGCACGUUCUCAUGGGGAACCAGGUGAUCUGGAAAAGCAGAGACGUGGACCUCGUCCAGUCAGCUUUUGAAGUACUUCGGACCAUGCUUCCCGUGGGCUGCGUCCGCAUCAUCCCAUACAGCAGCCAGUACGAGGAGGCCUAUCGGUGCAACUUCCUGGGGCUCAGCCCGCACGUGCAGAUCCCCCCCCACGUGCUCUCCUCAGAGUUUGCUGUCAUCGUGGAGGUCCACGCAGCCGCACGUUCCACCCUCCACCCUGUGGGGUGUGAGGAUGACCAGUCUCUCAGCAAGUACGAGUUUGUGGUGACCAGUGGGAGCCCUGUAGCUGCAGACCGAGUGGGCCCCACCAUCCUGAAUAAGAUUGAAGCGGCUCUGACCAACCAGAACCUGUCUGUGGAUGUGGUGGACCAGUGCCUCGUCUGCCUCAAGGAGGAGUGGAUGAACAAAGUGAAGGUGCUUUUUAAGUUCACCAAGGUGGACAGUCGACCCAAAGAGGACACACAGAAGCUGCUGAGCAUCCUGGGUGCGUCCGAGGAGGACAAUGUCAAGCUGCUGAAGUUCUGGAUGACUGGCCUGAGCAAGACCUACAAGUCACACCUCAUGUCCACGGUCCGCAGCCCCACAGCCUCGGAGUCUCGGAACUGACCCGUCACACACACCUGCCUAAAGACAGGGAUGGCUGUCCACAGGAUCCUCCAGCCCCGUGAGAGGGACUGUCCCUUGAGUUUCUCAACUGCUGGAAGGAGCUGUGUCCCAGCAAGGAAGGGAAACCAUCAGGGCUGGGCUCGGCCCUGUCAGGUUUGGGGCCUGUGUGCUUCCCAGACUCUCCCUCCAGCCGUUGGAAUCGCUGAAGAUGGCAAUGAAAGGCGGAGGGAUGAUGGGCUCUCUCUGUGUUCAAACUCCUUGGAGAGACGACUAGGAGGACAGCUUGCCUCCCAGGCCCCUUGUGGACUUAGACUCAAAACCCGCAGGAGAAACAGGUCCGACUCAGUAUGCAGUCGCAAUAACAUGUCUGCUCCCGAGGUUAACAUUCAAGCGUUUCUACUUUGAAAUUCAGCAAGAGUUUCUGGGCCUUAUGUUUGAGGGUACCUUUUGCUGCAGUUGUGAAUAUUCAGUACAUUGCCAGCUCUUGGUCACUGAGUGAUUGAGUUAGGGCUCCGCAAGAGACUUUGGGGAGUGAAGUGGAUCUCUUCCUCAUCUUUUGGUCCUCUGAAAUGUGUGUUCUGAAGCCAUGGGGCUCGUCUUCUGGGGUGUUCCCCUGCAGGUGCUGGUGAAGGUAACCUGGGGCUUAAUGAUGGAGUCCCUGAUCAUUUUUGCACAAGACAGGUUGCUGAGGGGUCGGCAAGCAUCUGACUUGCCCAAUCCCCUGGAUAUGGUGAGCCCCGCCAUGCUUUUAUUCUGUAUCGCUUUUGUCUUUAUUGCUGCUUUCAACAUUUACGUUUGGUUACAGUUAACUAUUUUCGGAGUGUGGUGAUUGAAGACAAUUUCAUCAUCCCACUGUACUUUUUUUUUUGAGAGGGAGUUUCACUCUUGUUGCCCAGGCUGGAGUGCAAUGGCACGAUCUUGGCUCACUGCAACCUCUGCCUCCUGGGUUCAAGCAAUUCUCCUGCCUCAGCCUCCAGAGUAGCUGGAACUACAGGUGCCCGCCACUAUGCCCAGCUAAUUUUUGUAUUUUUUAGUAGAGACGGGGUUUCACCGUGUUGGCCGGGCUGGUCUCAAACUCCUGACCUCAGGUGAUCCACCCACCUCAGCCUCCCAAAGUGCUGGGAUUACAAGCGUGAGCCACUGUGCCUGGCCCUUUUUUUUUUUUUUUUUUUUUUUUUUAAAGAGAUGGCAUCUUGCUAUGUCGUCCAGGCUGGUCUUGAACUCCUGAGUUCAAGCAGUCCUCCUGCUUCAACAUACAGCUACAGGUACCCCCCACUAUACAUUUUUAAUAAGGAUUCAUGGCUCAGAGGGAUUUUCUGAUGGUUUUGCUGAUUUGUUUCUAGUUUUUUUGUGUUUAUAUUUAACAUGAAGACCAAGUUUAUAUAACUAGGUAUCUGUAUAAUGCAACAACAUUGGAACACAAUAAAGAUGUAUUUUUGUAAA